ACAUUCUUUCAGACCCGGCCCGCUGCGGGGCGUUCCUGGGGGGUAGCCUCAAGGCCAGCGGGGUUCCUUCGGCUGCGUUUCUGUGGGAGGCCCUGAAACGCGCGGAGCUUCCCUCUGCCUCCAGGCUUUCCCAGCGAGAGUGAAAUUAAACUUGAAACUCGGAUCAACUGGCAGUCGUUGUUGGUAGAACGCCCUAAGGACCCCUCCCCGCGGGACGGAGGGAGGACUCGGGACAGGGAAUUGGCCCUGGGAGAAAACGCGCGGGGGGCGUCCGAGACGCCCCGUGAAAGCCGUGCCGACCCUUGGGAGGACUGACAGGUCUAGAGACACGCGCUGUCUGUUGUGGUGGGCCUCCCGGGAAUAAGUGAGGGGCUCUGUGUUUCGAGGAUGGUUCUAGCGCAGAGCCGGGUGUCUGCCGGGGUGGGCUCCCCGCAUUGUUCGGGCUCCGGCGGGGGCGGCUCUGAUUCCUUUCCAUGGCCCGCCUCCCACCCCGGGAAUCCCCAGUGCUCCUUUUCCACGGCUUUUCUGGCGUCCCCCCGACUCUCCCGCGGCACUUUGGCCUACCUUCCCCCAGCGCCGUGGUCCUCCCUGGCGACCCCCUCUGCGCUCCUGGGGUCCUCCUGCGCCCCCCCUCCUCCACCGGCGCGCUGCCCACAGCCGCGUGCCCUCUCCCCGGAGCUGGGGACCAAGGCUGGGCCCCGCCGGCCGCAUCGGUGGGAACUUCCGCGGUCCCCAUCCCAGGGCGCACAGGGUCCAGCUCCUCGGCGCCGACUCCUGGAAACAAUGAAAGGUAUUGUUGCAGCAUCUGGCAGUGAGACUGAGGAUGAGGACAGCAUGGACAUUCCCUUGGACCUUUCUUCAUCCGCUGGCUCAGGCAAGAGAAGGAGAAGGGGCAACCUACCCAAGGAGUCUGUGCAGAUUCUUCGGGAUUGGCUGUAUGAGCACCGUUACAAUGCCUAUCCUUCAGAGCAAGAAAAAGCGUUGCUGUCCCAGCAAACACACCUGUCUACGCUACAGGUCUGUAACUGGUUCAUCAACGCCCGCCGCAGGCUCCUCCCUGACAUGCUGAGAAAGGAUGGCAAAGAUCCAAAUCAGUUCACAAUUUCCCGCCGUGGGGCCAAGAUUUCUGAAACGAGCUCUGUGGAGUCCGUGAUGGGCAUCAAAAACUUCAUGCCAGCUCUAGAGGAGACCCCAUUUCAUUCCUGUACAGCUGGGCCAAACCCAACCCUAGGGAGGCCACUGUCUCCUAAGCCGUCAUCCCCGGGAUCAGUUUUGGCUCGUCCAUCAGUGAUCUGCCAUACCACUGUGACUGCAUUGAAAGAUGUCCCUUUCUCUCUCUGCCAGUCGGUCGGUGUGGGACAAAACACAGAUAUACAGCAGAUAGCGGCCAAAAACUUCACAGACACCUCUCUCAUGUACCCAGAGGACACUUGUAAAUCUGGACCAAGUACGAAUACACAGAGUGGUCUUUUCAACACUCCUCCCCCUACUCCACCGGACCUCAACCAGGACUUCAGUGGAUUUCAGCUUCUAGUGGAUGUUGCACUCAAACGGGCUGCAGAGAUGGAGCUUCAGGCAAAACUUACAGCUUAACCCAUUUUCAAGCAAAACAGUUCUCAGAAAUGUCAUGAUUGCCGGGGUGAAGGCAAGAGAUGAAUUGCAUUAUUUUAUAUAUUUUUUAUUAAUAUUUGCACAUGGGAUUGCUAAAACAGCUUCCUGUUACUGAGAUGUCUUCAAUGGAAUACAGUCAUUCCAAGAACUAUAAACUUAAAGCUACUGUAGAAACAAAGGGUUUUCUUUUUUAAAUGUUUCUUGGUAGAUUAUUCAUAAUGUGAGAUGGUUCCCAAUAUCAUGUGAUUUUUUUUUUCCUCCCCUUCCCUUUUUUUGUUAUUUUUUCAGACUGUGCAAUACUUAGAGAACCUAUAGCAUCUUCUCAUUCCCAUGUGGAACAGGAUGCCCACAUACUGUCUAAUUAAUAAAUUUUCCAUUUUUUUUCAAACAAGUAUGAAUCUAGUUGGUUGAUGCCUUUUUUUUCAUGACAUAAUAAAGUAUUUUCUUUAAAAAUUGUUGUAAUUCAGAGUAUUUCUGUUGAGGGAGGUGCUUCUUAAAAAUAAGUAGGAAUAUAGCACCCCAGUGAGCAGGAAGCUGGGGGGGUAGGGUGCAGUGUUAGGGGGUGUCACCAGCUCUUUGAAAACCUGUGGACAACAAGCCAGUUUGCAUAAACAGGAUGUGUGAUAUUUACUCUUGAUAGGAGGCAUAGCAGGCCCUUAGAGCUUUACUUAAACUGCAUGGCAAAUUGAAAUGAAUCAUUUUAGUGUUUAGCUAGCCACUAAAUCCCUUGCUGAUCUGUCCUGCGUAGUUUAAAACGUGGCCAUGUUAUAAAGAAAAGUCUUGAAGCAUCCGGUUAUUGCUGAGUUUUCAGAAGAAAACAACGCAAGCAAUCUCUUGCCCUUUUUCCACGUUACCCUUUAAAAUAACCUUUGUUCAGUGGUACAUUUAGUUAAGGCAUUUGUAUUCAAAUGUAGCAUAGUAUUUGCAGAGAAAUUACCUUUUAAAACAUCUCAAAAGUGUUUUCUAAAAUGAUGAAAUAAACGGUGGGGUUCUGUCUAUGGUGGGAUUGUCAGUUUAUUAGGUGAGUAUUUUCCAAGGUCUCAGUUUGUGAAAAAAUGGUGCUAUGUACAAGUGGAGUUUGUUGGGAUAGACAAUCACUUACAAAGCCCAGAUGGCCAGAAGGGAAUUGGUGUUGCUCCUUUCACUUGUAUGGUUGAGCAGAUUUGUCACAUGCCACAAAACCAUUCUUUGUAGUCAUGCUUAGUAUGAGCUUGCUUUGUUGUUACGGUCAUGUUCUUUCCAGCCCUGCCCCAGCUAUGAAUUGUCUAAGUGUGAGGGAGCAUCAGAGCUUCAGUAUUGUUUAAAGAAUGUAGAAAAAUACAAAUUUGUCUAAUUUUGAAACUAUUUUAGAAAGUCCCUACUGUAGAAAGAGCUAAACUCAAAGACUUUCCUUGUAAGUGAAAGAAAAAAACUGCUGAUGAUUACCAAGAGGCGUAAGAAAAUUAGGUGAGGGAAUGUUGUGCUCUAGCCUGUGGGGUGCAGCUUCGUAGGGCACAUCAGCUUAGAAUGGUCUGGCCUCACCUCAGAGAGUCACAGAAAUAGACAAAAACCCAAAAAGUACUAGUAAAGUAAAUACAAGGAACAAAAUAAACAUUAAUAAAAAUGAAUGACGCAAAGGUGAUCCAGAAUCAUUACUUGCUCCAACAGCUAGAUCAAAGGCUGAACAUUUUGCUUUAGUAUAGAUGAGGGAAAUGAGCAAGUCCUAAAAGGUUUGCCCUGUUACGGUGUUUCAUCACUCAUACUGGAAGGAGAAGGAAAGGAGCCAUAUGACUCAUUUAAAAGAAAAACUGUAAGUCACCUUAAAUUCCCUAUGUUUUACUUCAUUUUUUCCCUAUUGAGGUUGUUACAGGUCAUGGUUGAUAAUAGUUGGUGUUGAAUGAAUGUAAUCCAUUAUUUAAAAACAGGUACAUUUAAGUGAAAAGAUAAAUGUAAAAAGCUGUUCAUAUCAAAGCCAAAUAGAAAUGAUUUUUAUGCUUAUAAUUUACAUGGUGCAAUAUAUCUUUUUAAUUUGUUUACUUUU